CAGUUUAGAUGUAAAGGGUCAUCCUAAUCAGGUCUUCCUAGGUACAUAUAUUUAGAUACUAACCCGACUCUUAAUUUACCAUGGCCUUAUUUAUCUUCGGCAUUUGGAUGACUUUAAGAAAUAUGUAUACCUCUUAAGCCUUCGUUUCUCUGAAGCCUAUCUCAUUCUACUUGCUUCCCAUUCCCCUCCCCUGACACAUGCAUACAUACACAUAGAGAAACAUCAGUGAAGAAACAAAUACAGAUAUCCCUAAGUAAAACCAAUCACUUAGACUCUACUACAUCAUGGGAAAGGAAGGCAGAGUUAUCAUUAAACAUAUUUUCUGUGCUCUGGCAUACCUUUAUGAAUUCUAAUUAUCUAGCCUAAAGAUAAAUUUAUUUAUCUCCUGUUUUUGUGGGGAAGGCAUUAUCCUACUAUACCUGAAAUGAAUUUGGUUAACAAAGAUGAGUAAAUAAAAAGUGCUAUAGUAGUGCCCCCACCCAUCCCUGCUCCUGUCCUCUGAUUAAGGGAGUUAGUAAAUUCCUAUUUAUCCACAGAUGGAUAAAUGGAGGUAAUAAAGACAAAGAAUGUUAGAACUUGCUUAGAAGAAAAAAACGCAAAUUUCCAUAAAUUAUGAUGUUGACUUCUGGGUAGUCAAUUCCCGAUUAUCCACCCAAUGGAAGCUUCAGAUUAUAGAUAAAAACAGGUAAGUUAGAGUCCUGAUUCUGCUCAAGGGCUACAAUAAGUUUAGUUGCUGAGUGAAUAGACAGCAAUGUAUCCCAUGCUCUGCUGUGGCAGUGCUAAGCUGUGAAAGUCAGCAAAUCUUAUUUUUAGGAUUGAAGCUCUCUCCUGACCAUAGGCAGCAAACACCUCCAUCUGUGGAUAAACAGGAAUUUUACUGAGCUCCUCCACAGGAAUGAGGAACAAAACUAUCUGAGAUGUAGCUUGUGAUAGUUCGAGGAUUAAGUAAAACCCUUGUGUUGAGUCAUUUGCUAAUGUAAUUACCAUUAGUGACAACAUGCUUUUCCCAAUGAAGAUGCCAAGAGAAAAACAAGAAAACUAAAUCUACUUUAUGGUGAAUCUAGGAUGAGUAGAACCAAGAAACACUGUGUCUUUUGGUAGCUAUCAAAUUAUGCUUUCUUUGCCUAAGGAAUUUUAAGGCAGAUUUCCCUCCAGAAGGGGGGAUGCAAGAAAAGUACUUUGUGCUGGUUAGGAUCUACUACUUACUUCUGUACAGUAACCACCUAACUGAUGUUCAGGCCUUCCCAAUAACGUAGCUCACUGCUAGUUUGAUGAAACUUCAUACAACUGUGCACUGUUAUUAAUCUGUUAAAAAACCUUCCAUGGUUUCUUCAUCACCUACCAGAUAAAUUUAAAACACCUUACUGUGAAACUUAAUUUGGCCUUUCACACCUGACAUUCUAUUAUUCAUUUUAGAGGAGAAAAUCCCCAAGCCUCCCUUCCAACCAAAUUGAUUUACUUCCUGUCUUGGAACAAAUAUUGCCCUUUCCUACCUUGUUUCUUCUGUCAGCAGUGUUCAAACUCAGCUUUCUAAAUUCAGCUUUUUAAAACUCUGCCCUUGUUUCAAAACUUUCUUAUAAAUAAAUGCAAUGUUCUAGACACUGCUAGAUGCUGUGGCUGGAUACAGAGAAGUAUAAGAAAAAGCUGCUUGUGAGAGGCAUAGUGUUUGGCUAGGGAGAAAACAUGAACUACGCACAAGUUAAAUGAGAAAAAUUAAAUGGUAAUUCAGACGACAGUGGAGAAAAUGAAAAUAAGGCAGUUCCUAAUUGUAAAAUUAUCCAGGUAAAAAUUGCUUUGGGAGUUUGAAGAAGAGACAUUUAAAAACAUUGAAAAUUAUCUUACAGAGAUAGGGUUUAAUCUGAAUCCUAAAAGAUUUUUUAUGGAAAUGGUAGGGUUUUCUGUAUGAAAGCAGUGUCCUGAGGAACAUUAAAUAAUUUCACAUCCGGUGAGCAAACUGUCUUGAAAAGAACGCAGAAUUCAUGUAAAGAAGUAAUGAGAGAUAACAUUUGAAGGGUAUUUGGAAGCUCACUAUGUAGGACUAGUGACAAUUUUAUCCUGAAAGCCAUAGAGAAGAAUGAAAGACCCUUGAGCAAGAAGAAGAUAUGAUCAAAAUAGUUUUUUAGAAAGACAUCUGAAAGUGAUACUAAAGGGGAAGAGGCUAGAAGCAGUUAAAUCAGUUUGAAAGCUAUUGCAGUAGUACAGGUAUGCAAUAAGUGCCUCUACUUUUUUUAUCCCUGUGUAUUAUAAUUGUUGGUUUGUGUAUUAAAACCAGACUGUGAAUGCCUCCACAAGGAGGGCUUAAUCCUCUGUCUUUUCAGCACGUGGAAUACUCCUUGUGCAGAUGAAUGUUUGUGUAGCUCAGGUGAAUAACAGAUUAAAAUAGAUGGAGAGAUUACAAAGAAUGUAUCAGCAGAAUUGGUGACAUAUUAGAGGAAUGGGGAACAAAAUGAAUCAAAGAUAAUUUUUGAACUUGGAAGAAUGGUGGUACUAUUAACAGAAAUAAAUUGAGAAAGGGAGCCAAUUUUUUAGGAAGAUGGGAGUUCUGUUUAGGUAUUUUCACUUUUAGAAGACUAAUCCACAUCCAGACAGAAAAAACAGUUUUGGUAAUUGGAAAUGAAGUCACAGGUGGGAGCUGUUCAUCUAGAGAAGAAAGAUUGUUGAUAUUCUAAGCAUCUGUAGGUCAUCUGCUAUCAAGAGCUUGUCAAGAAAAAAGAGAGGGCAGCAGCUGAAACUUGAAGAAUAUCAACAUUUGGGGGUGGGUGGAGACAAAGAGGAGACACAGAGCGAAUGACCGUAAAUGUGGGAGGAAAGCCAGGAUGGUGUGGUAUUACAGGUGCUAAGGUAGAAAAGGUUAACAAUGUGGUCAGUAGUGUCAGUGGCUACAAAAGCCAAAGAGAAGUCAGAAAAAAACCACUAGGCUUGACAAUGUAAGAGACUGUUGAUAACCUGUGAAAGUGUUAAUGCUAUUUGAGUAAAGUUGAAGAGGGAGAAGUCAGAUUUUAUAAUACUGAGAAUGACAGUAGGAGGUGAGAUAGUGGAAACCACAGGUUAAGCCUUUUGCCUGAAGAAAUCUGUGACUGACAGAAACAUGUACCCUGUUAAAAACUAGAUUGAGAAGACUUGUACAUAUUUUUAAGUGGAGGAGAGAGCAAGAUCUUGAACCUACAAGAAUAAAGACUAAGAAAACAAAACAUUUUAUGGGUUUGGAGGUGAGAGUAGAAUUAAAAGCAUAGGAUUAACCUUUUGAAGGGAGAAAGAAAAAACUCAUACAGGAACCAAAUAUACAUGCCGAGAUUUAGCAAUGGAAUGUAGGGAAGAUGGGGAGAUAACAGCUACUGUAUUAAUCUUAUGCCAUUUAUCACACCCAGUCUUGCAGAGUUAGCUAUUUGUGUACCCAUUUAUGUUGUUAUUUGUGUGCCCAUCAAAUACUUCCCUGCUACUGCCAGAUAAGGAUCUUCUCUUAAUAUUUUGGCAUCUUCCAGAAUAGCACCGAAUAGGUACUUAGUAGAUACUUUUUGAAUGAAUGAAUGAUAUCCAGAUACCCAAAAAUUUGAGACUCGGGACUUUUCAAAAUUAUUGAAAUUAUUCUGUCAGAUCCAGCUUUUUUUCCCUCUUAUUCUACUACUAUUCUGUAGUCCCAUAACCUUUUCAGGUACUUUGAUAGCAUUUGAAAUUAUUAUUCAGUAGAUAAUGAUUGCGUUUUCCAAAUUCUAGAAUAAGAAGGAAAAUACUCAGCGUAUACUUUUUUCCACUUUGCCUUUUCUAAAUGGAAUUUAAAUGAUUUCAUUUUACUUCAUAGAGUGAAGUAAUUUAUGUGAUGGAAUAGUUCUAUGAAAGAAUAAUGUAAUUUUGACAAAUCCUAAACAUUUUAAGUUUCUAAAUGACUCUGUUGACUAUAGUUAAUUAUUUGGCAUUGGCAACUAUUAUCUGAUUCCCAAAAUUUACACCAAACAUCAAGGGAGAAACAUAUUCAAAAAUUGAAACUCUAAUUUCUGGUAAUAUGCCAGACUAGAUAACCUCAAAAAUAAUAUAGAGACAAUUAGAAAUUUCACAUUAGUGUAACAAACACUUUUAACUAAAUGGCUGAACUCUCAGGAAGGAAAGGAAGUCCCCAGGAAGAGGAAAAAGAAAACAAAACAAAACUCGAAAUCUAGACAGUAAACUCUCCUGGGGGCAUUUACCAAUUUUAGAAUAUUAGAGUUAAGUUUUAAUGGCUAUAAUAUAGGAGAUGGGCCAAGGGUCUAACAAAGUAAAGAAUUAGAACUGAAAGGCCUAUGUCAUUCUUCCCCAUAGGACUGGGCCUCUGAAUGAGUUACACCUUCAGUGAGAGUUGAAGUUAGAAAAAUCUCUCAUUGACAAAUAUAGACAAAUCUUAAUUAUCUUAACCUGGACUGGUAGGUGAGGUGGGAGGGGGAAAAACAUCCUGAGAAUUCAUAAUCACAGUCGUGAUAAGGUAAAACUGAAAUAGUGGACAACAUUAAUAUGUCAGAGAUAGGAAGUGGGUAAUUGGAAUUGAAGUAUUUUAAGAUUGUUGAAUUAUUCGAGAAAAGGAUAGAAAUCGUGAUUAACUUUAGGCUUUAAGUAUACGUGUUAAAAUGUUAAGGACAACUACUAGAAGAGUAAAAAUAGAGUAUUUUUAUUGAAAUAUUUGAAAAUAUUAAAAAAUAUUUUCAAAAGCAAUACAGAAGAAAAUGGAAUUUUUUAAACCUGAUUAACCUGAUUUUAAAAAAAAGAAAAUCAGAAAAAAAUGGGGAAAAAAAUAGAAAAUACAGUAAGAUGGUAAAAAUAAAAUCCAAUUAUAUCAUAAAUUAUAUAUGAAAAUGUUAAAAGAUAAAUAUUGUCAGACUGGAUUUUUUUUAAUGCUAUGAAUGAGAGAUCUAAAACACAGGGACCUAGGAAAGUUAAAAGUAAAGGCUUGGAAAAAGAAAGCUGGUGUAGCCAGUGAAAUAGAAUAAGACUAUCAAAAAAGUUACUGGAAUAAAGGAGGUCCCUAAAUAAUGAUAAAAUAUAAAAAUCACUAGGAAGACAUAACAAUCUUACAUGUACCCAAUAACAAAACCUCAAAUUUUAUUUGGCAAAAAUGGACAGAAAUGGAUAAUUCUACAGUCCUAUCUAUAAAAAUUAGUAAGGAUAUAGAGAAUAUUCAAAAAUGCAGUAAGCUUGAUUUAAUGGACAUAUAUAGAAUCCUGACUCCAACAAUUAGUCUUCUCAAGCACAUACAGAAUCUUUAUAAAAACUGGCAAUAGACCAGGUCAUAAAACAAAUCUCAACAAAUUUCAAAGUUAUACGGAUUGCAUUCUCUAAUAACAGUUGAACUAAGUUAGAAAUUAGUAACAAAAAUUUACUGUAAAAACCUUUAUUUUUGCAGUCUUUUAAAGUUACUUGCAAAUAACUUGUUAGUCAAAAAGGAAAACAUAAUGGAAAUUAUAAAAUACUAAGCAAUACUGAAAAUAGUGUAUAUCAAAACUUGUGGAAUAUCACUAAAAUAGUUCUUAAAUGAAAUGUGUAGUCUUUUACAUUGAAAAGGGCAAAAGCUACAAAUCAAUGAGCUAAGCGUUUAACUCAACAAGUUAGAUAAUAACAAACCCAAAGAAAGUUUAGGGAAAGAAAGAAUGAAAAUAAGAGUAGAUAAUGAUGAAAUGGAAAAUAGAAAUAAACAGAAUCAAUAAAGCCAAGAGUUGUUCCUUUAAAAAGCCUAAUGAAAAUAGAUGAAACCGACAAGAUUUGCUAAAAAGAGAAAAUAUAAACAAUGUUGACAUGAAAAAAGGGUAUAAUUAUAGAAAAUUAGAGAAUUGAAAAAUAGACUAUUAUAAAAAAGACCUUUUUGAUAAUAUAUUUGGAAAUUUAGACAAGUGGACAUUUUAAGAAAAAUGUAACUUAAAAUUGUAGAAGCAAUAAAAAACUGUAAUUAGGCCUGUGACCUGUAACCAUUAAAGAAACAGAGGCUAGACACAGUGGAGCACACCUGUAGUCUCAGCUACUGGGGAGGCUGAGUUGGGAGGAUCACUUGAGACCAGAAGUUUGAGGCAGUGAGCUGUGAUUCUGCCACUUUACUGGGAGUGACAGAGCAAGACCCUGUCUUGAAAGAGAGAGAGAGACAGAGAGAAAGGAAGGGGAGGGGAGGGGAGGGAAGGAAGGGAAGAAAGGAAGAGAGAAGAGAGAGAGAAAUGGAAUCAGUAGUUUAAAAUCUACCACUGAUUAUGGUUUAAUUUCUCAUACAGCUUGACUUCAGAAAAAUAAUUAAUGUCAAAGCACACUUGCGUUAAUAUUUCCAAUCAGUGAUAAUUCAGUUUUUCAUAGCAAGUGAAUAAAUUAGCAUUCUGGCAUCUAAAUUUAAAAGCAAAAAGUACCUCAGUAUGGCUAUUGAAUCCAUAUUGAGUCUCACAGGUGGACAUGGUUCCCUUAGAGUUUUUAAGUCUUACAUCCUUUGUUUAGGGAUUUCCUUAGAACAGAAAAAGUGUAGAACAGAAGAUGUUCUUGCAAAAAUUUUCCUUUUGGGGAUGUAUAAUUUAAAAACUAAAGGAAAUUAAGCUGAACAGAUAUCUAAAGAAAAUGAAUAAGAUAUCAAGACUUAAAUGUAAUUAUGUUUAAGUGUGCUUCUCAAUAAAAUUUGGAAAUUUGUGACUUAAUUUGAGACAGGGUCUCACUCUUGUCAGUCAAGCCCUGCCUCUUCCACCUCAGCGCCUUGCCUCCCAGCCUCAGCGCCCCCUACCCGUAGUAGCUGGGACGACAGGUGCAGUCGCACGCCGCCACGCCCAGCUAAUUUUUGUAUUUUUUGUAGAGAUGGGGUUUCUCACCAGGUUGCCCAGGCUGGUCUCGAACUCCUGAACUCAAGUGAUACACCCGCCUCGGGCCCCCAAAGUGCUGGGAUUACAGGCGUGAGUCACCGUGCCCCGCCAAUUUGUGACCUUUUUAAAUAGAAUGAUGCAUAGAAGGAAAAUCCUCAAAACUUUUAAACCUAAUUUCCCAUGAGGCUUAUUUAUCAUAAUCUCAAUUUUUCUGUGAUAGCCAUGUCACUAAUAGAGAGAUCAAAAGAAAAAGAAAAAAAUUAGAAGAAAAAAUAACAAUUUAAUAUACAUAAAGGAGAGUGGUCCUAAACUCAACCAGUUGGUUGAAUUUAAUUCCAUGUGUGAGUUAGAGGUAACUAGAAAAUUUAUUAAUUUAUUUUGUAUUAAAUUGAACUAUAUGAAAUUGCUGGUAUUUUACCAUUUUAAUCUACCAAAAAAAGGCAGUUCUAUAGGGCUGUACCUAAUAGAGUCAUGAUUAUAAGCACAUGUGUCUAUUGAGUGGGGGUAGGGGCAGGUGUCCAGACAAAGUAUGCUUAACUAUUUUUUAGUUGUUAAAAUAUAUUUGCCAUUAUUUAUUAUCUUUUAUUCUAUCUUAAUAAUCCCUGCAGACAAGCAAGAAUGGGUGCAAAUGGUUUAUAAAAACAUUGUGAGAGAAAUACUUAAAACAGAGAGAAUUCUACCGGUUAAAAUUUGUUUAAAAAUUUAGACACAAUCACAAGAUGAUUCCAAUCUUGCAGUGACUUAAGACCUCCAUUAUGGAACACUAGUAUCAGUAUUAGUCAGGAAUAUAGUUUAGUUUGGUACCCAAAACUAAAACGCAUAUAAUCAAAGAAUAUGAACUUAUAUAAAUGUAUUAAUUGGAAAUCAAAGAAAUGUGAGUAAUUAGGCCUGGUUUUAUGGAAGUAGAUGAAUUGAAGUUGAUAUUGAAGGUCAUCUAAGAGUUGGCAGAUAUGUAGGUGAAAAAAGCAGGCAUGUGAGAAUGAAUGUGGCCAGUUUGAGAUUAGAGAUCAUCUGACUGAGGCAAAUUGUAGAAAACUGUUGGCAGAAAGGACUAAAUAUGCAAAGUAGGGCCAGGUGAUUUUUUUCCUAAUGUCUGACUAUCUAAAGAUCUCUAGGAAGGAAAUUUCAUCCAGAAAGUAAUGUUUUAGGGAGAUUAAUCUGGUAAUGAUGAGUAGGAUAGCUUUAAGCAGGGAGAGACUGGAGUCAGUAAGAGCAGUUAGGUGCUUCCUGCCAUAAUCUGCAUGAGAAGAUAAAAAGCCCUAGAUUAGGAUGGUGGAUGGUAGUGGAAAUAAGACAAAAUGAAGCCAACAGCCAUUUCGAAGAGAUACUUAGCAGUGUGUGUUGGCUAAAGGGGGGCAAAUCAACAUCAUAGGCUCCUUUCUUUUUUAUUACCUUCACUAAUGGGUGAUGUUGAGUGUAAAUGAUUUUGUUUUUGUACAGUGUCAUGUGCAUAUUUAGUUCUUGGUAAAUGAUUAAAUUUUCAUCUUUAUAUUACAGGUUUACAUAUUUGUAUGUUUUCUUUUUUUAAUGUCCUCUAUUAAUAUUUGUUUGGGAAAUAAAACCCAAACAGAGGCUCUGGCAUAAUCAAGACUAAAUCUUUUUUUUAAUGUUCACUGACUACCAAAAUGAUGGUAUGAAUAAAUCUACCAUUAUACCCCCAAUUGUACAUGAAGCAUAUUAACAAUGAGAAUAUAUUACUAAAUCAGUUACAGAAAAAGUUAUAUAUGAAGCAUAUUAAUAAUGAGUAUAUAUUAUUAAAUCAGUUACAGAAAAGGUUUAAAUAAAGGUGUUAGGCCCUAUCUGUAGAUUAGAAGAGAUAGUUGAUGACAAAAUAAAACUCACCAAACUGAAGUUGAUACCUUAUAAAUACCAAACUGAAGUUAAUACAUUAUAAAUAAUUGGACUGACAUGUUCAAAAUAGUCAUUUUAUGCUGAACAAUGCUUUGUUGUUUAGUAAUUGUUCUUUGCAAAACCUAAAAUAUUAAUGCUUUUUAUCUCUGUUCAUCUCAUACAACUUAUCUAAGUACUUAUCUCCCCACAUAGGUAUACUGAAGAUUAGUGGCAUUGAAAGACAUGGUUUAUUUUGGAGGGCUCUUGUCACUUUUUUGUUCAAGGGAUCAGUAUUAGAUAUUCUUUAUAAGUUGUUUCCUGUUUUGUUCACAUUUUUUCACCAUUAACUUUUGUCAUUAAGUUAGUAAACUUUUGUCCCUUGUUAUUGUUUUGCCUCACCUCUCUGUGUUUCUUGACUAGAAUGUUUUUAUCAGCAUCAGCAUUCAAGGAUUGAGUUGUUCUUUACAGGUUUUGUGUGCAGAAAACACCUCAAGAGUAUGACUUAAUUCUCUUUAAAAUAUGAAGAAAACUAGAGUCUCUGUGAUCAUUCAUCUUAUUUUUUUUCUCCAUUGCAGCCCAUUAUACAAAACACAUGGAGAACAGGAUAGAAUGCAUGGCAAUUAAAGCUGUCUCUAAAGCCAAACUGCAUGGAUUCUAAUCCUGCCCCCACCCUUUUUACCAGCUGUGCAAACAUGGGCAGAGUAAUACAUGGGUGAUAGUUCCACCUCCAAAGAGUUGUUUUGAGGAUUAAAGAUGUAACUUAUGUAAAACAUGUAGCAAAUAAUAAGGCAUAAUACAAGGUUGGCGCAAAAGUAAUUGUGGUUUCACAUUUUUUAAGUUGCAAAAGCCACAAUUACUUUUGCACCAAACAUGACAGUUUGAUGUUUGUACUUGUCGUUGUUAUGUUUUCAUCAUCAUCAUUAAGAUACCCACUUGUCAUCACUAAGAACUAGAUACGUGUUUUCUAUCUGAAACUUAAGAUAACACAUAAAUAUCCCUGAGCUAUUUUCUUGGCCUUUUCAGUUGAGAGUGUUGUUUGCACUAAAAGUAUUCUCUACCAUCUCAUCCAACAUUGUCAUGUGAAGCCCUAAGUUGAAGAAAUGGAAUACUUGUGGGUGGUAUUCAGAUUCCUUGGCUGGGGAAAAAAAUUGUUUUUCUAUUAUGUUAACAAGAAGAAAUAUUAAAUAUUAAAAAUAAUAAUAAAUUUACUGAAGCAAGGAAGUGGUGGGGAGACUGGAUGGCUUUACUUUAUGAGAAUUUACCACAUUUAUGUACUUAGCACCAAUUUGUACAUAUUGGAGUGUGUGGGGCAUGCAAACUUGAAAGGACUACUUGUUUGAGUGAAGUACUGCAGUCUGAGUGAUACAAAUUGGGUGAAUUAAAGUGGCUCUGGGGAUUUGUAUUUCAGAGCAGCUGGAUGCUUGUGGCUGACAGUGCAUAGGCUUUAAGGCAGUAAAAGUGGGAUACAGCAGAAAGUAUCCUACUGAAAAUGGUGGAUGAAGUUUAUAAAAACACCCAGGUGCUAUAGUGUUAGCAGCCGUAUAAAUGCAGUAUGUGAUUUUUCUUCUCUUUGCUCUUGUCACUUUUUCUUUAUAAUAUUUUUCUAACUCUGUCUUUUAAGUUCCUAUUACCUUUAGGAGUCCUCCAGCAAAAAAAUAUGAAACCUUAUUUUCAUGAAAGCCUUUUUUGUUUCACAAUUUGCCAUUUGUUAUUAAAGCCCCUCUACUGAAGAGCUACAAACCCAUUUCCUCCUACUAUUUCAUCCUUCCUAUUCUGUUUCUUAAAUGUCUUCUGUGCCUUAAAUGUCUUCUGUGCAUCCUAUGGAAGAAGAACCCUCCUAAUUCAGAAUUCACAGCAUGGAGAGAGAAGUUAUUUGCUUAUUUCAUUCAUUAAUAACUAGAGCCACCAACAUACCACAUCCUAUUUAAUGUUGUCAUUAUUUACAAAAUGCAAGGGAAAAUAGAUUAUAGUGAAGUGGACUCAUUCAUAGCAACACUAUAUAUGCCAAAAUUUCAGUGACUUGAAUGGGUACACAAACAGUUUGGUUUGUAUUCAAUGUUUUAUCAUGUUUUGUUGAAAUGUUGAUUUUUAAAAAGGCUUUUGAAGUAAACUGAAGAAUUCACUUUAUGAGAAAAACAUUAGAAACUUGUUUCCUACCUACAAAUAUCAAAAUUAUUAAAGAGGCAUGUGAAUAAUUAUAAUUGAAAGAGUAUUUACAUUUAUUCAUGUUUUAUAAUUCUGUGCAAAAAAUUACUAAGAAUUGGUUCAGGUUGCCAUUAAUAUGAAGUGCUUAGAAUCCUGUAUAUGCCAAAGAAACUGCAUCUGUGACAUGUAAUAUUUUUCUGUUCUAUUGUAACUUGAGAAUUUUACUAUGAUAUUUUAGUUUCUUAUAUAAUUGUUCACCAAAUUAAAGCUAUAAAUAUCUUUCUACAUUUUAUUUACCUUUCCUGCUGAAUUUCCUCCUCUGAACUUACUUUAUUCCCUUUUAAAUUUUGCCACCAUCCUCAGAGAGAGUAAUAAUUGUUACUAUCUCAGGGGCUACAGCAAAGAUUAAGUAAGUUAGAUACUAGGCCCAGUACUUAGCACAUAAAUUCUCAACAUGAGCUAAAAUUCGCUGGGUGUGGUGGCACGCACCUGUGGUCCCAGCUAAUCAGGAGGCUGAGGUGGGAGGAUCGUUUGAACAUGGGAGGUAUAGGCUGCAAGGAGCUGAGAUUGUGCCACUGCACUCCAGCUUGGGAGACUGAGUCCAUGUCUCAAAAAAAAAAAAACACACACACACACACAAAAAAAAAACUCAAUAUGAGCUAAAAUUAUAAUAAAACUAUUUUCCCUAGACAAAUUAUUCACAAAGAGGUGCUUAAAUAGCUUUUAUAAUGUAACUCUUUUAAAAGAAAAAAAAUUUAAAUUAUUAUCUUUACUUGUUUUUUACGCUAUGGUAACUAAUUCUAAAAAUGAUAGACAUUAUAAGAAAUUUAUGUUAUUUAUAAUAGUUAAGUAUAUGCAAAUAUUAUAUGGCAUAUGACCUUCGGUUAAACGAGAUUGAACAAAAAGUAAAUGUAAUUGAUGCCUAUAGAUAUUUGACCGUAUAGUAAUGACAUUGUGUAGCAGAUACCUUUCUCAUUUAAGAUAUUUUCGGAGUCUUUUGGAACCUAACCCUCAGUUAAUAUGAUAGACAUUUCACUUUACUCUCUUUCCAAACAUAAUAACAUUCCAGAUUUAUUCUGUAUCACAUUCAUUAUUCAAAAUCCUGAAAAGAAAAUUGACCUGGUGGAGUUGGCUCAAGCCUGUAACCCUAGCACUUUGGGAGGCCAAGGCGAGUGGAUCAUUUGAGCCCAGGAGUUAGAGACUAGCCUGGGUAAGAUGGUGAAAUACCCUUUCUAGAAACAGGCAUGGUGGCACACACUUAUAGUCCCAGCUACUCAGGAGGCUGAGGUGGGAGGAUCACUUGAACCCCGGAGGUGGAGUUUGUAGUGAGCCCAGAUCAUACCACUGCACUCCAGCCUGGGCGACUGUCUUAAAAAAAAGAAAGAAAAAGAAAAGCAUUAAGAAAUACCAGUAAGUGUAUAUCUAUGGACUUUCAAUACGAUUUGUACCUUUUGGUGACGCAUGUCUGACCAGGUGGUUUUUCAUUUUAGAGUUAAAAAAAAAAAGUCCUUACAAGAGAAGAUUAAUGAGUUUAUAUGUUUUGGUGCAAAAUUAGCUUUUUGGAAGAAAGGGGUUCUUUAAAAUAUAGUAGUAUUGUAGUGUCAUUUCCUUAGCAUAUACAUUUUCUUCUGUCACUGUCCUUAUAUUGGCCAGUAUUAUCUGAACAUGUCUGCCCCAGUUCCUCUCAGACUUUACCUCCUACUAUUUGUUCCCACUCACUGGCACCAAUCCCACUGGCCUCUUUGUUGCGGUUUACCUUAGAAGCUUUGUACUAGCUUCCCUCUACCUGUAGUCUUCUUCCCUGUUAAACCUGCAAGGCUGACUUCCUUACCUCCUAAAGUAUUGACUCACACCUCACCUUUGCAGUGCAACUACCUAUUGAAAAUUACUGUACCUAUUCAUCUCCCUGACUACUUUUUAUUUCCCCUAAAACACUUGUCACCUUCUAACUUACUCCUUAGGGUCCUCUCAAAUACAUGAUAGGAAUUUUUGGCAUUUACUCCCUGGUAAGUGAACCAAAGGCAGUGUAUACACUAUUAGGUUCUAAGGCAGAAAUUGACUUCUGUUUGUUGAACAGGAACAUCCUCCACCAAAAGUAUAUUUGCCCCUAUAAUUAUCCAAUUUUCAAUUUCUUUGCCACACUUUCCAAAGAAAGUGCGUUGACAUAGAGGAAUAUGUGUAUGUUGAGGAAAUGAUAGUACUCUAUUUUGGAUUUUAAAAGAUUCUUCCUUCCAGAAAGCUAAUUUUGCCUCAAAGCAUAUAAACUCAUUAAUCUUGUCUUUAUCUCUGUUUGGUCUGGAUAACCCAGUUUAUUAAAUGGCGAAGACCAGGACAGAAAAGGUGAAAUGGCUUACACAGAAUCGUACAUAUCAUUGGUAGAGCUGCUAAGAAAAACAUCCAGAUGUUCUCUUUGUUCAAUACAUCAUUCUAUAUGGAGCUGUAUUGGAGGUUAUCUCUCAUCAUUUUAAGUCAUCACAUCAUCUGAGGUCAUAUCCAAUGGCAAAGGAAAUGAAGAGAUACAUUUAAAACUUAACCAGGCUUUUUAUAACUCUUUUUGCCUUUCAAUCUGAAGAUGAAAAAUAUUAUGUUUAGAGAUGAGAAAGUGAGGCAGUUUCAGGCCUUUAUCUGAAACAAUACUGUAUCUCUCUUGUCUCAUCAGUCUCAGAGAAUGAGCAUAUUUUAAAAUGACUGUAAUUAAAUAUUGUAACUAUGAAAAGAACAUUAAUUUUACAGCAGGUGAAAAUAAUGCAAUAGUAUGUAGCAUGAGUGGGGGUAGAGGAUACAGCUGUCUAAUUUUGGUCUACUGGAACUAGUGUAGAUUUUCCUUCAAACUGAGCAGAAAUGUAGCUCUUAGAGCAUAGUAGCAGCUUUCCUUUCUGCUUACAGAUUUAAAGUUAAAGGCACAAGUUUAAUAUGCUGUUCGUUCUGUGACUAAUCCAGCAGGUUGCUCAUUCCGCUCUUGCUAAUGCUGCUACCUUGCUUCUAAGUGGACAUUGGUACUUGGGGUAUUUAUUUUUCUGUAUGCUUUGAAGUAGUUAUGAAUCUUCUGAGAACUAAAGAACUGGGAUUCUCCAAAGGCCUAUUCUACACUAGCAGGUGAGUGGUAUUAUUGUGGGGGUUGAGAAAGCAACAAAGUGUAAACUUCUUUUCAUUAGGUGAUUUAGCUUUACCUUAUUUCUUCCCCUUCUUUCCCCUUUUUAGUGGAAAUUGUUCAAACUUCAGGAAUGAUUUAAUAUCUUCUUUCUGGACCCGAUAAUACAUCAUAUAAGCUACAUCAGCAUUGUAUUUUUUCCCAUAAUACAGAAAGAGAAUUUUUUUUUUAAUUUUAUUAUUAUUAUACUUUAAGUUUUAGGGUACAUGUGCACCAUGUGCAGGUUUGUUACAUAUGUAUACAUGUGCCAUGUUGGUGUGCUGCACCCAUUAAUUCAUCAUUUAGCAUUAGGUAUAUCUCCUAAUGUUAUCCUUCCCCCCUCCCCCUACCCCACAACAGUCCCCGGAGUGUGAUGUUCCCCUUCCUGUGUCCAUGUGUUCUCAUUGUUCAGUUCCCACCUAUGAGUGAGAACAUGCAGUGUUUGGUUUUUUGUCCUUGCGAUAGUUUGCUGAGAAUGAUGGUUUCCAGUUUCAUCCGUGUCCCUACAAAGGACAUGAACUCAUCAUUUUUUAUGGCUGCAUAGUAUCCCAUGGUGUAUAUGUGCCACAUUUUCUUAAUCCAGUCUAUCAUUGUUGGAAAAAAGAGAAAAGAAAACAGAAGUAUAACAAUACCAUAUUUAUUGGAGUUUGAAAUGUGGCCACUAAUUUUAGUCAAUAUAGUUUCAAAUAGUUAAAAGCAUUGAAACAUAUUCAUUUAAUGAGUUUGUAUGCCUGAAAACUAAAAUUGGAUGUAUGGAAGAAAGUGAGGAAAUUAAUUUCAGUUUUUUUUCCUUAGCCAGAACAUUGCAAAUUAAGGAAAUGGUUUACUAGAUCAUUUUAUCCCAGCUAAUGAAAUUUAUUUUUCCCCCAAUUUAGUUUCUCUGUCAAUUAUUCAGAAAUUAAAACAUACUAUAUUGUAAUAUUAAAUCUCCAGUGUCUUCUAAUUUGAUAUGAGGUUACCUUUAUAGGUAAUUAUUAGAGGAAAGGUGAGAUUUUUUUUCUACCUUCACCAGCCCCAUUCCCUGCCUGCCUUGCCCCUAGCCACAUAGAGUCAUCUAACUUGGAUAAUUACUCUGUAAAGUCAUAUUCCUGAAGUCUGGAAGUCUUUCUGUUCAAUGUGCUCCAACAAGCUGAUUUACUUAAAUUCAGUGCUUUGUGCCAUUCCCAUGAAUCUGAGCUAAUUAUGCUGCCAUUUUUCAGCGAUGUGCAUUAGAAGUCAUGUGUGCCUAAUUCUGAGAACAGCUUUGCACAUUAAGGCUCAUUUGACUAGUGAUGGUUAGAGAGAAGUUAAGGGACUUACAGUUACUGGUCAUAAUUUUAAAAUACAGUAGUAGUAUGGAACUCUCUUGUACUGCAAGCAUACAAGAUGCUAUGUUGUCAGCCUCUCAGUCUUUAGGAAUGUUCCAAUUUGGCUUGUGCCUUACCAGUCAAGAUGUCACAGAGAAGAUAUGUUUAGUCAUGGAAAAGAAAAUCAGUGUCCAGCAUGCAAAGAUAGUAAAAGGGUAAGCACUUCCAGUUGGAUUUUCAUAGGAGGAAUUGAUUUGUGUGCAUUACUGGAUCUGUGUAAAAUGGUGUCCUUUUGGCACUAGGUGGAUAUACAUUUCAGUAAAUGUUUUUUCUUGCUGCAGAUUAGUGUAAGACAGUGAAAUUUUCAGUAACUGAGGGAAGGCAGUGGUUGGGCAUCUGUUAAUAGCCUGAAAGUAACUAAUGAGGAUGUGCAGUCAGAACGAUUGAUUGAAUAGCUGCAGUCCUGUGUAUUUCUUUCUUGCUUGCUCUCUGCAAGCUGUGGAGAGGGAGGGGGAAGAGCAAGACACAGAGAGGGAGCGAGAGAAAAAACGCUCUCUCUUAAGUGGAAGUAGCACGGAUCCCAGGGGCCAGGAGGCCAGAAAUGGAAGUUUAAACUGCAUCUGUCUUUUAAAGGGAGAACAGCAGGAAUCAAAAUGUCAGUCUCCGGAGUUACGAUUUACUCCUUGUUUUCUAAGAUCUGGAAGAUAACACAGAAUACUUUUUUUAGGAUGUGGCUUUUUUUUCCUUGUCCAUGUUGAGAUUAUCUAAUGUUAUCUGAGAAGCUGGAUUCCUUUAUGUCUGUCAGUUGAAGUGGCGAUGGGAAGCAGUUGUGAUAAAGAGGUACCAGCAGAAAGGUCCCCUCGUAGACGGAGUAUCUCAGGGACCAGUACAUCAGAGAAACCCAACUCCAUGGACACUGCAAAUACCUCACCCUUCAAAGUACCAGGAUUCUUCAGCAAGCGCCUGAAAGGCUCCAUCAAGAGGACCAAAAGCCAGUCAAAGCUUGACAGAAACACGAGCUUUCGGCUUCCAUCCCUUCGCAGUACAGAUGACAGGUCUCGUGGGCUGCCUAAACUAAAAGAGUCACGUUCCCAUGAAUCCUUGCUGAGCCCAUGCAGCACAGUGGAAUGUCUGGAUCUUGGUAGAGGGGAACCUGUAUCAGUGAAACCACUUCAUAGUAGCAUCCUUGGACAAGACUUCUGCUUUGAGGUUACCUACUUAAGUGGAAGUAAAUGCUUCAGCUGUAAUUCUGCUUCUGAGAGAGACAAGUGGAUGGAAAACCUUCGCAGGACAGUUCAACCUAAUAAGGACAAUUGCAGGCGAGCUGAAAAUGUUCUUCGUUUAUGGAUCAUUGAAGCCAAGGACCUUGCCCCUAAAAAGAAAUAUUUCUGCGAACUGUGCCUUGAUGAUACCCUCUUUGCUCGUACAACCAGCAAGACCAAAGCAGACAAUAUUUUCUGGGGCGAACAUUUUGAAUUCUUCAGCCUUCCACCUCUUCAUAGUAUCACAGUUCACAUUUACAAGGAUGUGGAAAAAAAGAAAAAAAAGGACAAGAAUAAUUAUGUAGGGCUAGUCAACAUCCCCACUGCCAGUGUGACUGGUCGCCAAUUUGUAGAAAAGUGGUAUCCAGUGAGUACACCUACACCCAACAAAGGAAAGACAGGAGGACCUUCUAUUCGGAUUAAAUCACGUUUCCAAACUAUCACCAUUCUGCCUAUGGAGCAAUACAAAGAAUUUGCAGAAUUUGUCACCAGCAACUACACCAUGCUGUGUUCUGUCCUUGAGCCAGUAAUUAGUGUGAGAAAUAAAGAGGAGUUGGCUUGUGCCUUAGUGCACAUUCUUCAAAGUACUGGCAGAGCCAAGGAUUUUCUGACUGACUUGGUGAUGUCUGAGGUGGAUCGUUGUGGAGAGCAUGAUGUCUUGAUCUUCAGAGAGAACACUAUUGCCACCAAAUCCAUUGAGGAAUACCUCAAGUUGGUGGGACAACAGUAUCUUCAUGACGCACUGGGGGAGUUUAUCAAAGCUUUGUAUGAGUCCGAUGAGAACUGUGAAGUGGAUCCCAGCAAAUGUUCAUCUAGUGAACUGAUAGACCAUCAGAGCAACCUGAAAAUGUGCUGUGAGCUGGCUUUCUGCAAGAUCAUCAACUCUUACUGUGUUUUCCCUCGUGAGUUGAAAGAAGUGUUUGCAUCAUGGAAGCAGCAGUGCCUGAACCGUGGCAAGCAAGACAUCAGCGAGAGGCUCAUCAGUGCCUCAUUAUUUCUCCGUUUUCUGUGUCCAGCCAUUAUGUCUCCCAGUCUUUUCAACCUUAUGCAGGAGUAUCCUGAUGACCGCACAUCUCGGACUCUAACUCUUAUUGCCAAGGUCAUUCAGAACCUGGCCAACUUUGCCAAGUUUGGUAACAAAGAGGAAUACAUGGCAUUCAUGAAUGAUUUUUUAGAACAUGAAUGGGGUGGAAUGAAGCGCUUUCUUUUGGAGAUCUCUAAUCCAGACACCAUCUCAAACACCCCAGGCUUUGAUGGUUACAUUGAUCUGGGCCGAGAGCUUUCAGUUUUGCAUUCCUUACUGUGGGAAGUAGUUUCCCAACUUGAUAAGGGUGAAAAUUCCUUCCUACAGGCGACCGUGGCAAAAUUGGGGCCUCUCCCUCGUGUUCUUGCUGAUAUUACCAAGUCAUUGACUAAUCCUACGCCAAUACAACAGCAACUGAGACGCUUCACUGAACAUAACUCCAGUCCAAAUGUCAGUGGAAGCCUCUCCUCUGGGCUGCAGAAAAUAUUUGAAGACCCCACUGACAGUGAUUUGCAUAAACUAAAAUCUCCAAGCCAGGACAACACAGACAGCUACUUCAGAGGGAAAACAUUAUUGCUGGUUCAGCAAGCCUCCUCUCAGAGCAUGACUUAUUCUGAAAAGGAUGAAAGGGAAAGUAGCCUUCCUAAUGGUCGGAGCGUCUCCCUCAUGGACCUCCAGGACACUCAUGCUGCUCAAGUGGAGCAUGCAUCUGUCAUGCUUGAUGUGCCUAUACGCUUGACCGGAAGCCAGCUUUCCAUAACCCAGGUGGCCAGCAUCAAACAGCUGCGGGAAACCCAGAGCACUCCCCAAAGUGCACCCCAAGUGAGAAGGCCCCUGCACCCAGCCUUGAACCAGCCAGGUGGCCUUCAGCCCUUGUCGUUCCAGAACCCUGUCUAUCACCUCAAUAACCCAAUUCCAGCAAUGCCAAAGGCCUCUAUAGAUUCCAGUUUGGAGAACCUAAGCACUGCCAGUUCCAGAAGCCAAAGUAACAGUGAAGACUUCAAGCUCAGUGGACCCAGCAAUAGCAGCAUGGAAGAUUUCACUAAACGUAGCACUCAGAGUGAGGACUUCUCCAGGCGGCACACGGUGCCAGAUAGACACAUACCUCUUGCUUUGCCACGACAAAAUAGUACUGGGCAGGCCCAGAUCCGAAAAGUGGACCAGGGUGGGUUAGGUGCCCGAGCCAAAGCCCCACCAUCCCUGCCACACAGUGCUUCUUUACGUAGCACCGGGAGCAUGUCAGUGGUGUCCGCAGCCCUGGUGGCCGAACCUGUGCAGAAUGGGAGCCGGUCCCGGCAGCAGUCCUCUUCCUCCAGAGAGAGCCCUGUUCCCAAAGUUAGAGCAAUCCAGAGACAACAGACACAGCAGGUUCAGUCACCUGUGGACUCUGCCACAAUGUCCCCAGUAGAGAGGACAGCAGCCUGGGUUCUGAACAAUGGGCAGUAUGAAGAGGAUGUGGAAGAAACUGAGCAAAAUCUAGAUGAAGCCAAGCAUGCUGAGAAGUAUGAACAAGAAAUUACUAAACUGAAGGAGCGCCUGAGAGUUUCCAGCCGGCGACUGGAGGAAUAUGAACGCCGCUUGCUGGUGCAGGAGCAGCAGAUGCAGAAGCUGCUGCUGGAAUACAAGGCCCGACUGGAGGACAGCGAGGAGCGGCUCCGAAGACAGCAGGAAGAAAAAGAUAGCCAGAUGAAAAGCAUCAUCAGCAGGCUAAUGGCUGUGGAAGAGGAACUGAAGAAGGAUCAUGCUGAGAUGCAAGCAGUUAUUGAUGCAAAGCAGAAAAUAAUUGAUGCACAGGUCAUAAAUGGAGAUGAGAUUAUUCAAACAGGAAAAACGGAUCGUGUCCCUGGAUUCAGCCAACACCAGACUGAUGAGCGCGCUGACCCAAGUGAAGGAGCGGUACAGCAUGCAGGUCCGCAAUGGCAUCUCCCCCACCAACCCCACCAAGCUUUCCAUCACGGAGAAUGGUGAAUUCAAAAACAGCAGCUGCUGACGGGCUUUGUCUGUGGAAGGAGACAGAAGGAAAUUGACCCACUCUCCUAUCUCCAGACCUUUACCUAGCCCCUCCAGGUUUACAGAAUGUUGCUACUUCACAAUGGCGAUGUGGUGAGAAACUCCUGAAUGAAGAAAGGAACCUUGUCUUUCAGGGCAUAAGGCGGCGACUUCCAAGGUCAAUGCUUUUCCCCCACAUCUCUAUGUACAUAGGGAACUUAGUUCUGGGCCAUGUACAGAAAAUAUCACUGUAAUAUACCAAAAGGAAGUUAAUAAUGUAGAUUACCUUUUUGAUUAUUGCUAUUUUUAUUAUUGUUUUCCUCUUGUUGAAAGCACUGCAGUUGUUACAGGAAGUAAAGUAGGAACUGUUGUGUGAGCGAGACAUGAGCCUGUAGGUUCAGUAGGUAGAGACCAAGCAUCUAUCUGAUAGAAGCACAUGGAGUGCAAUAGGACAUUGUGAGAAGGAAUUUUUCAGGGAUUCAUCUACUAGUUUAAAAACCCCACUCUGGCCCUCUUGUCCUUUCAGAAAACAUGCAAAUACCAAGAUCCAUACAAAACAAUAAUUUAUUCCACUGAUCAACCAAGACUGGUUCUGGUUGGACAGCUAAUCUGAUUUGGGGAUUCACUGUUUCAGAGGACACAGACAAAAGCUGUUGCAUCAAAACUGGACUUUAGGAGUAAUUUCUAUUGAACUCCUGUCAAUAUGUUUAUUUCCUCUGUCUACAGCAGAUGGGAGUCUUCUCUUUUAGACAGGGGCUUUUUGUUUUUAACCCCAAUUGUAAUAAAGGGUGUUCUUUUUCCUCUUUAGAGUUUACAAAACUAUAAAUAUUUGUGUCUCCACAUACCAUCUUCAUCUUCACACAUUCACUGUGCUUUCCUCCCCAUAGUGGGAGCUGUCAUCACCAACAGGGUUUACUCUCCCCUGGAGAGGUUAUUUAAAUAGCUGUCCAUAAGCCAUCCAGAUCAACACCCUUUCUUCCAUACAGAAAAGGGCUAACCAUACCACAGCUGGAAUCUCUGAAUAUUUCCUAUUAAAAAUUUUUUCUAUGUGUUGUUAUAAUUUUUGUUUGGGAUAAAGACUCUAUCCAUUGUACUAGCAAAUCUAUGGGGGGUAAUUUUAUCUCCAUCUUUAACUUUUAAAGUACUUCUUCCCCUUAUCCCCUCAAUAAAGAAAGGAAAUCCAAAUUUGAAGCAUCACUCUCUUAAAAGAAAAAGAAAAUAAUGGAAAGUGUCAGGAUGGCACAUUCCAGUUAUUAUUCCAAUGCUCGUAGAUCUGACAAUAAUGACCCAAUUUCAACACUUGUCAUCCAUAGCCUUAUUAUUAUAGAACAGAAAAAGUCAUGGAAACGAAUUCAUUUCCUUUUUUCCAGAGGUGUGCAAUGUCAUCUUGAAUGCAACCUUGAUUACCAGAAGUAUGGAAGGUUACAUGUUAAACAGACAUUAUAUAUACAAAUAUAUAUAUAAUAUAUAUUCACACAUAUGUACAUAUAACUGCACAAAUAGGAAAAGUUCAUGCCUUCUAUGCUGUUCAGAUAUAAUGUUAAAAGGGUCUCAAACCUCUUUAAGCAAGAUCUAAGUAGUUGUUUUAUAUUGAGAAAGCAACAAUGUUUCUCGAAUAAGUUGAUGUUGAUUUUAAAUUAUAAGCUUUAAAGAAUUUUUUUUCUAGAAAAAGGGGAUGGAAAAAAAAGGACCUGAGGGAGCCAUAUGCAUCAAGUGAGUGUUUCUCCAUAACAGAAUAUUUAUAAGAGAACAUGUAUAGUGCCCUCUUUUGAGUGAUGCCGACAGACACCAAGCCCUCCUUUUCACCAAGUCCCAGGCUUGCAUUCCAGCCUCUUGAGCUCUGCCCUCUCUCAGGUGGAUCUUUGUGUUGGACCUUACGUUUCAGCAACCUCACCAUGGCCACAUAACCCACAACCUUUUAAAACAGUUUCUUUCAUAGCAAUCCCUGUUUCUGCCAGACAGAUCUAAAAUGGGAGUUUCUCACUGUGUUUAUCUGAUCUGCACACUUUAUAUCCAGCUGUUUUGGCACUUUUACGUUUUCUUCACCUUUGGUUUUGGUUUGCAAAUUCUUACACCUUCUCUCCAAGCGGAGGGCACACUGUGGUCAAAAUCACUUAUUUUAUUAGGAAAAAGAGGUAACUGUUCCAAAGUGUAGUGUCCUUUGUUGAAGGAGGAGGGAUGUAAGCAUAGAUUUGUUCUUGUUUCUGGCUAUUCUCAGCUCAAGCCAUGUUUAAUUCAUUCUUUGUAAAAGCCUUCAAUUGUGCCACAGAAAACCUGGUAAGAGAAUUGUCAGUUUCAUUGGCCAUAAGUAUGUAAUGUGGGUGAUGUCUUGCCAUUGAGGUUUGGAAGCUCUUAAGUGCCGAUUAUGGAUUACAGAGGGCUGAUAAAAUUACUUAUAUUGGGAAUUGAGAGAAGCCCCAAAAAAUCAAAUGUGCUUUUGAUGGAUAGAGUGUAUCUUAUUAGCAUUAUGGGAGCUCCUUAGAGGGCUGUCUUCACUGAAAGAUUUAAUGCCCAAAACAUUUGGACAGAUUAUGCAGCCUUCUACUACCAGGUUAUCUUGAAUGAAGAAGAAAUAGUAAAAAAUAAUAAUAAUAGAGCAUUACCAAUAAGCUAAAAGUUCAGAGUUGCUGAUAGAUGUUAAAUGUUAAGUUAUCCUGUGAGCCUACUCCUGUCCAACCUUUUUUCUCAGUAUUUCUUUAGAGAAUGCUGCAAUCUGUAUAAGUUACUCUGAAGGAUUUUUUAAGAAGAGAAGCCACCAACAGGUGAUAAUUUUUAUGGAGAUGUUUCUUAAUUGGCUUUCCCUCAGUUCAAGUAGGUAAAUAACUUUGUUUGCUGGGAGGAGGUACAUGGCUGAAGAGAGGCAAAUAGAUUAAGAUAGCAAUGUCUUGCACUUCCUGUUUCCCUCAAAACAACACCACAUUGUGGGGCGCAGGAUAGAUCAGGGUUGAGUGGAAUUUGGAAUUCAGGUGAAGUGCUUGUAAAGUGCAUGUCUAGCUGACAACAGACUUGACCAUUAAUGAGGACAGUGUUGGUAGGAGUCAGAAAAGAGCUUCAUAUUCCCCUUUUAUAUUACUGAAGCAAUAAGCAAUCUGAGCUGAAGCAGCAAAAAGAGUCACAUUUCCAUCAGGUCAUCAUAUUCCCUGAGUCUCUGCAGCAAAAGCCAUGUCAGAGGGGAGAUUAUAACUAGGUAACUAUAACAAGCACUUGAGCACUUACCAUGUUCCAAGCACUAUCACCAAGGUACUGUUGGGGUUUAUGGCAGUCUAACGGUAAGAAAAAUGUGGUAAAAUGAGGUAAUCAUGCUGCUAUAGCUUUUUGCUUUUUUUCAUAUAGUAUCAAGUUGGUCAGAAUUAGCUUUCUCUGACUGGUCUGCUUCCGUGUUUCUCUGUGAUGGUGUUAAGAUUAUGAAAGAAAAAGAAGAUUACCUAAGACUGCUACAAGUGUUAACUAUAUGCCCUUAAGAAUGAGCUUGACUUUGGAAGUAAAGCUUUUCAGAUCUUAGUCUACCCGGGGCCUUUGUUGAUGGGUCUGUGGUUCUGUAGACCCCUGGCUUUCACUGUGUUCUCAGAGGUACACCAGAUUGAGAGCAGAGUUCUUCUUUGGAAGUCCCAGAGCAAAAUAACUGCCAUCAAGUGAGUUUGCAUUCGUAUUUGUUUCCCCUUCCAUAGAGGGUUAGUUUUAGUUACCUCUAGCUUGGAGUUCCUGAGAAGGCUGGUUAUAGGACUGAGCGUGGGAAAGGAACCCUCUUCAGGAUUACCUCAGUCCCAUCAGUCUACCCCAUUGUGACAUUGAGCCCAACACACACGCUUGACACCAGACUAGACUUGUCACAGGGCCAAACCCAACAGCCACAUGCCAUAGCUUCACUGCAUUUUCAGCUACACCUUUGGAGGCCACCUUCUCCUAUCAACUGUGGAAAGCCAGAAGGGCUCCCUUCUCCAUUCUCCUUCCCUUUUUCAAGUCUAAUAGUGAAAUCUCCUGCUUACCCCAGCAGUAAAUAGUUGCCUUCCUACCCCUUACCUGGGGGCCGAUAAUUUGAGAUACUUUGUUUUUUCAAUGCGUCAGUUGAAGGAUUUAGUUUCUUAAAAGCAAGAAAUGUUGGAGUGUUGAAUUUUUAAAUAGAAUCUCUUUUCAUGUUUGAAUGAUUGUUAUUAGUUCUAGAAGCAUUCUCUUUGUCAUGACCCGAUUAUGUAUACUCUUGGGUUUAGGAAGGACAAAAGUGAUGAAAUUUGCAUGAGAUAGAAUAAAUAUCUUAGGAGGAGUGAAAGAACCUGAGGAAGAGACACGACCCUAAGGGAAUGAAUGCAUAAGCAGUCUUCUCAGUAGCCCAGAGUUUCCAGGAAACAGGAAUAUUUAUAUCCCUUGCCCACUCUUAAAAUACAUAGAUACAUAAAAAGGCAGUCUCUGUAGACAACACAUGCACACACCCACACAAAACAUAAUUCCUGGGGCUUCCUUUUUCUGAAUGUUAAUCCAUUUUAUCGAGCAGUGAUUCCCAAACUUUGAGAUUUUCAGAUUUUAUGCUCUCGUCUGUUAGAUUUUAUGACAUUCUAUCAUCCUAAAAAAUGUACUAUAUGUGUUAUAUGUAUAUAUAAGUUAAAGCAACUUGAAAUUGACUUGGUUUGGCAUUGUCUCAAGAACCCUAGAUAUCAUUAUUGAUACCAUGGGGAAUCAUAGAAAUAAAGUUGAAUAUCAUUGAUCUGAGAGUAGGAUCCAGAAAUAAGUAGUUUCAGUUCCUGAUCAGUUAAGCCUCAAGUGUUUGAGUAACCAACACAGCAAGACUUGGGAAAUGCAGUGAGCACCCGAGGAAAGGAAAGUGGUAGUCUUUGCCUGCAUUUCAGCAUGCAUUUUCCUUUCCUACUCAGUUGCUAUCUUCCACUUAAAUACCCUCAUUUGACCCUAGGAAGUUUUUUGUUUUUUUUUUUAGUUUGAGACUUAAAACCAGAUUUAUUUGUUGUUGUAGAGAGAUUUCCACAGAAGUUGUGUUUUAGGGACCUCCAUCAUCUUUGUGGGGGUACAGAUAUUUAUGUGUAAAUAUCAUUUUAUGUGAUUUCCAAAUUUUCGAGGGAAACAUUUCAAUUCCCAGUUCAACAAAAGGUUAAAUACUAAUUGACUCAAUGACCACCUUCAGGAAAGUUAAAUAGUAAAUUAGGUUAAAUUUUGACUGGUGCUUAGACAUUUCCUAGUUAUAUUAACUUAAGCAGACAGCAGCACAUUAACCUGAGUUACACCUGUGAGGAAAUGACCUUCUAAAUUUGAUUUUGUUUUUCAUCUCCAGGGCCUUAAUAAGAGUGUGUUAACACACGACUAUUUUACAAUGAUAGCUCUAAAUAAUUUAUUUUUUAUUUCAAGAAAGAGAAAUACACCUUAGAAAAACAAAACCCAAGAUUUUAUUUUAUUUUUAAAGCCAUAUUUUUGUGCUAGUAGCAUUUAGAUUAUUCCGUAUGUGAGAUCCGUAUCAGCAUUUCAUUACCUGGGUUUGUUCUAAAGAAGAUUUAUUUUUGUUCUGUGAAUAAUUUUUGACAGUUCUUGUACAUGUACAGAUAUAGAUACGUUUGAGGUCUUUUAUUGAUAUUCCUACAAAGAAUACAAAUAAACUUUAACUUUAAACA